GACCCCGGCAAGCCCGCGCACUUGGCAGGAGCUGUAGCUACCGCCGUCCGCGCCUCCAAGGUUUCACGGCUUCCUCAGCAGAGACUCGGGCUCGUCCGCCAUGUCCGCCGCAGACGAGGUUGACGGGCUGGGCGUGGCCCGGCCGCACUAUGGCUCUGUCCUGGAUAAUGAAAGACUUACUGCAGAGGAGAUGGAUGAAAGGAGACGUCAGAACGUGGCUUAUGAGUACCUUUGUCAUUUGGAAGAAGCGAAGAGGUGGAUGGAAGCAUGCCUAGGGGAAGAUCUGCCUCCCACCACAGAACUGGAGGAGGGGCUUAGGAAUGGGGUCUACCUUGCCAAACUGGGGAACUUCUUCUCUCCCAAAGUAGUGUCCCUGAAAAAAAUCUAUGAUCGAGAACAGACCAGAUACAAGGCGACUGGCCUCCACUUUAGACACACUGAUAAUGUGAUUCAGUGGUUGAAUGCCAUGGAUGAGAUUGGAUUGCCUAAGAUUUUUUACCCAGAAACUACAGAUAUCUAUGAUCGAAAGAACAUGCCAAGAUGUAUCUACUGUAUCCAUGCACUCAGUUUGUACCUGUUCAAGCUAGGCCUGGCCCCUCAGAUUCAAGACCUAUAUGGAAAGGUUGACUUCACAGAAGAAGAAAUCAACAACAUGAAGACUGAGUUGGAGAAGUAUGGCAUCCAGAUGCCUGCCUUUAGCAAGAUUGGGGGCAUCUUGGCUAAUGAACUGUCAGUGGAUGAAGCCGCAUUACAUGCUGCUGUUAUUGCUAUUAAUGAAGCUAUUGACCGUAGAAUUCCAGCCGACACAUUUGCAGCUUUGAAAAAUCCGAAUGCCAUGCUUGUAAAUCUUGAAGAGCCCUUGGCAUCCACUUACCAGGAUAUACUUUACCAGGCUAAGCAGGACAAAAUGACAAAUGCUAAAAACAGGACAGAAAACUCAGAGAGAGAAAGAGAUGUUUAUGAGGAGCUGCUCACGCAAGCUGAAAUUCAAGGCAAUAUAAACAAAGUCAAUACAUUUUCUGCAUUAGCAAAUAUCGACCUGGCUUUAGAACAAGGAGAUGCACUGGCCUUGUUCAGGGCUCUGCAGUCACCAGCCCUGGGGCUUCGAGGACUGCAGCAACAGAAUAGCGACUGGUACUUGAAGCAGCUCCUGAGUGAUAAACAGCAGAAGAGACAGAGUGGUCAGACUGACCCCCUGCAGAAGGAGGAGCUGCAGUCUGGAGUGGAUGCUGCAAACAGUGCUGCCCAGCAAUAUCAGAGAAGAUUGGCAGCAGUAGCACUGAUUAAUGCUGCAAUCCAGAAGGGUGUUGCUGAGAAGACUGUUUUGGAACUGAUGAAUCCCGAAGCCCAGCUGCCCCAGGUGUAUCCAUUUGCCGCCGAUCUCUAUCAGAAGGAGCUGGCUACCCUGCAGCGACAAAGUCCUGAACAUAAUCUCACCCACCCAGAGCUCUCUGUCGCAGUGGAGAUGUUGUCAUCGGUGGCCCUGAUCAACAGGGCAUUGGAAUCAGGAGAUGUGAAUACAGUGUGGAAGCAAUUGAGCAGUUCAGUUACUGGUCUUACCAAUAUUGAGGAAGAAAACUGUCAGAGGUAUCUCGAUGAGUUGAUGAAACUGAAGGCUCAGGCACAUGCAGAGAAUAAUGAAUUCAUUACAUGGAAUGAUAUCCAAGCUUGCGUGGACCAUGUGAACCUGGUGGUGCAAGAGGAACAUGAGAGGAUUUUAGCCAUUGGUUUAAUUAAUGAAGCCCUGGAUGAAGGUGAUGCCCAAAAGACUCUGCAGGCCCUACAGAUUCCUGCAGCUAAACUUGAGGGAGUCCUUGCAGAAGUGGCCCAGCAUUACCAAGACACGCUGAUUAGAGCGAAGAGAGAGAAAGCCCAGGAAAUCCAGGAUGAGUCAGCUGUGUUAUGGUUGGAUGAAAUUCAAGGUGGAAUCUGGCAGUCCAACAAAGACACCCAAGAAGCACAGAAGUUUGCCUUAGGAAUCUUUGCCAUUAAUGAGGCAGUAGAAAGUGGUGAUGUUGGCAAAACACUGAGUGCCCUUCGCUCCCCUGAUGUUGGCUUGUAUGGAGUCAUCCCUGAGUGUGGUGAAACUUACCACAGUGAUCUUGCUGAAGCCAAGAAGAAAAAACUGGCAGUAGGAGAUAAUAACAGCAAGUGGGUGAAGCACUGGGUAAAAGGUGGAUAUUAUUAUUACCACAAUCUGGAGACCCAGGAAGGAGGAUGGGAUGAACCUCCAAAUUUUGUGCAAAAUUCUAUGCAGCUUUCUCGGGAGGAGAUCCAGAGUUCUAUCUCUGGGGUGACUGCCGCAUAUAACCGAGAACAGCUGUGGCUGGCCAAUGAAGGCCUGAUCACCAGGCUGCAGGCUCGCUGCCGUGGAUACUUAGUUCGACAGGAAUUCCGAUCCAGGAUGAAUUUCCUGAAGAAACAAAUCCCUGCCAUCACCUGCAUUCAGUCACAGUGGAGAGGAUACAAGCAGAAGAAGGCAUAUCAAGAUCGGUUAGCUUACCUGCGCUCCCACAAAGAUGAAGUUGUAAAGAUUCAGUCCCUGGCAAGGAUGCACCAAGCUCGAAAGCGCUAUCGAGAUCGCCUGCAGUACUUCCGGGACCAUAUAAAUGACAUUAUCAAAAUCCAGGCUUUUAUUCGGGCAAACAAAGCUCGGGAUGACUACAAGACUCUCAUCAAUGCUGAGGAUCCUCCUAUGGUUGUGGUCCGAAAAUUUGUCCACCUGCUGGACCAAAGUGACCAGGAUUUUCAGGAGGAGCUUGACCUUAUGAAGAUGCGGGAAGAGGUUAUCACCCUCAUUCGUUCUAACCAGCAGCUGGAGAAUGACCUCAAUCUCAUGGAUAUCAAAAUUGGACUGCUAGUGAAAAAUAAGAUUACGUUGCAGGAUGUGGUUUCCCACAGUAAAAAACUUACCAAAAAAAAUAAGGAACAGUUGUCUGAUAUGAUGAUGAUAAAUAAACAGAAGGGAGGUCUCAAGGCUUUGAGCAAGGAGAAGAGAGAGAAGUUGGAAGCUUACCAGCACCUGUUUUAUUUAUUGCAAACCAAUCCCACCUAUCUGGCCAAGCUCAUUUUUCAGAUGCCCCAGAACAAGUCCACCAAGUUCAUGGACUCUGUAAUCUUCACACUCUACAACUACGCGUCCAACCAGCGAGAGGAGUACCUGCUCCUGCGGCUCUUUAAGACAGCACUCCAAGAGGAAAUCAAGUCGAAGGUAGAUCAGAUUCAAGAGAUUGUGACAGGAAAUCCUACGGUUAUUAAAAUGGUUGUAAGUUUCAACCGUGGUGCCCGUGGCCAGAAUGCCCUGAGACAGAUCUUGGCCCCAGUCGUGAAGGAAAUUAUGGAUGACAAAUCUCUCAACAUCAAAACUGACCCUGUGGAUAUUUACAAAUCUUGGGUUAAUCAGAUGGAGUCUCAGACAGGAGAGGCAAGCAAACUGCCCUAUGAUGUGACCCCUGAGCAGGCGCUAGCUCAUGAAGAAGUGAAGACACGGCUAGACAGCUCCAUCAGGAACAUGCGGGCUGUGACAGACAAGUUUCUCUCAGCCAUUGUCAGCUCUGUGGACAAAAUCCCUUAUGGGAUGCGCUUCAUUGCCAAAGUGCUGAAGGACUCGUUGCAUGAGAAGUUCCCUGAUGCUGGUGAGGAUGAGCUGCUGAAGAUUAUUGGUAACUUGCUUUAUUAUCGAUACAUGAAUCCAGCCAUUGUUGCUCCUGAUGCCUUUGACAUCAUUGACCUGUCAGCAGGAGGCCAGCUUACCACAGACCAACGCCGAAAUCUGGGCUCCAUUGCAAAAAUGCUUCAGCAUGCUGCUUCCAAUAAGAUGUUUCUGGGAGAUAAUGCCCACUUAAGCAUCAUUAAUGAAUAUCUUUCCCAGUCCUACCAGAAAUUCAGACGGUUUUUCCAAACUGCUUGUGAUGUCCCAGAGCUUCAGGAUAAAUUUAAUGUGGAUGAGUACUCUGAUUUAGUAACCCUCACCAAACCAGUAAUCUACAUUUCCAUUGGUGAAAUCAUCAACACCCACACUCUCCUGUUGGAUCACCAGGAUGCCAUUGCUCCGGAGCACAAUGAUCCAAUCCACGAACUGCUGGACGACCUCGGCGAGGUGCCCACCAUCGAGUCCCUGAUAGGGGAAAGCUCUGGCAAUUUAAAUGACCCAAAUAAGGAGGCACUGGCUAAGACGGAAGUGUCUCUCACCCUGACCAACAAGUUCGACGUGCCUGGAGAUGAGAAUGCAGAAAUGGAUGCUCGAACCAUCUUACUGAAUACAAAACGUUUAAUUGUGGAUGUCAUCCGGUUCCAGCCAGGAGAGACCUUGACUGAAAUCCUAGAAACACCAGCCACCAGUGAACAGGAAGCAGAACAUCAGAGAGCCAUGCAGAGACGUGCUAUCCGUGAUGCCAAAACACCUGACAAGAUGAAAAAGUCAAAAUCUGUAAAGGAAGACAGCAACCUCACUCUUCAAGAGAAGAAAGAGAAGAUCCAGACAGGUUUAAAGAAGCUAACAGAGCUUGGAACCGUGGACCCAAAGAACAAAUACCAGGAACUGAUCAACGACAUUGCCAGGGAUAUUCGGAAUCAGCGGAGGUACCGACAGAGGAGAAAGGCCGAACUAGUGAAACUGCAACAGACAUACGCUGCUCUGAACUCUAAGGCCACCUUUUAUGGGGAGCAGGUGGAUUACUAUAAAAGCUAUAUCAAAACCUGCUUGGAUAACUUAGCCAGCAAGGGCAAAGUCUCCAAAAAGCCUAGGGAAAUGAAAGGAAAGAAAAGCAAAAAGAUUUCUCUGAAAUAUACAGCAGCAAGACUACAUGAAAAAGGAGUUCUUCUGGAAAUUGAGGACCUGCAAGUGAAUCAGUUUAAAAAUGUUAUAUUUGAAAUCAGUCCAACAGAAGAAGUUGGAGACUUCGAAGUGAAAGCCAAAUUCAUGGGAGUUCAAAUGGAGACUUUUAUGUUACAUUAUCAGGACCUGCUGCAGCUACAGUAUGAAGGAGUUGCAGUCAUGAAAUUAUUUGAUAGAGCUAAAGUAAAUGUCAACCUCCUGAUCUUCCUUCUCAACAAAAAGUUCUACGGGAAGUAAUUGAUCGUUUGCUGCCAGCCCAGAAGGAUGAAGGAAAGAAGCACCUCACAGCUCCUUUCUAGGUCCUUCUUUCCUCAUUGGAAGCAAAGACCUAGCCAACAACAGCACCUCAAUCUGAUACACUCCCGAUGCCACAUUUUUAACUCCUCUCGCUCUGAUGGGACAUUUGUUACCCUUUUUUCAUAGUGAAAUUGUGUUUCAGGCUUAGUCUGACCUUUCUGGUUUCUUCAUUUUCUUCCAUUACUUAGGAAAGAGUGGAAACUCCACUAAAAUUUCUCUGUGUUGUUACAGUCUUAGAGGUUGCAGUACUAUAUUGUAAGCUUUGGUGUUUGUUUAAUUAGCAAUAGGGAUGGUAGGAUUCAAAUGUGUGUCAUUUAGAAGUGGAAGCUAUUAGCACCAAUGACAUAAAUACAUACAAGACACACAACUAAAAUGUCAUGUUAUUAACAGUUAUUAGGUUGUCAUUUAAAAAUAAAGUUCCUUUAUAUUUCUGUCCCAUCAGGAAAACUGAAGGAUAUGGGGAAUCAUUGGUUAUCUUCCAUUGUGUUUUUCUUUAUGGACAGGAGCUAAUGGAAGUGACAGUCAUGUUCAAAGGAAGCAUUUCUAGAAAAAAGGAGAUAAUGUUUUUAAAUUUCAUUAUCAAACUUGGGCAAUUCUGUUUGUGUAACUCCCCGACUAGUGGAUGGGAGAGUCCCAUUGCUAAAAUUCAGCUACUCAGAUAAAUUCAGAAUGGGUCAAGGCACCUGCCUGUUUUUGUUGGUGCACAGAGAUUGACUUGAUUCAGAGAGACAAUUCACUCCAUCCCUAUGGCAGAGGAAUGGGUUAGCCCUAAUGUAGAAUGUCAUUGUUUUUAAAACUGUUUUAUAUCUUAAGAGUGCCUUAUUAAAGUAUAGAUGUAUGUCUUAAAAUGUGGGUGAUAGGAAUUUUAAAGAUUUAUAUAAUGCAUCAAAAGCCUUAGAAUAAGAAAAGCUUUUUUUAAAUUGCUUUAUCUGUAUAUCUGAACUCUUGAAACUUAUAGCUAAAACACUAGGAUUUAUCUGCAGUGUUCAGGGAGAUAAUUCUGCCUUUAAUUGUCUAAAACAAAAACAAAACCAGCCAACCUAUGUUACACGUGAGAUUAAAACCAAUUUUUUCCCCAUUUUUUCUCCUUUUUUCUCUUGCUGCCCACAUUGUGCCUUUAUUUUAUGAGCCCCAGUUUUCUGGGCUUAGUUUAAAAAAAAAAUCAAGUCUAAACAUUGCAUUUAGAAAGCUUUUGUUCUUGGAUAAAAAGUCAUACACUUUAAAAAAAAAAAAAACUUUUUCCAGGAAAAUAUAUUGAAAUCAUGCUGCUGAGCCUCUAUUUUCUUUCUUUGAUGUUUUGAUUCAGUAUUCUUUUAUCAUAAAUUUUUAGCAUUUAAAAAUUCACUGAUGUACAUUAAGCCAAUAAACUGCUUUAAUGAAUAACAAACUAUGUAGUGUGUCCCUAUUAUAAAUGCAUUGGAGAAGUAUUUUUAUGAGACUCUUUACUCAGGUGCAUGGUUACAGCCCACAGGGAGGCAUGGAGUGCCAUGGAAGGAUUCGCCACUACCCAGACCUUGUUUUUUGUUGUAUUUUGGAAGACAGGUUUUUUAAAGAAACAUUUUCCUCAGAUUAAAAGAUGAUGCUAUUACAACUAGCAUUGCCUCAAAAACUGGGACCAACCAAAGUGUGUCAACCCUGUUUCCUUAAAAGAGGCUAUGAAUCCCAAAGGCCACAUCCAAGACAGGCAAUAAUGAGCAGAGUUUACAGCUCCUUUAAUAAAAUGUGUCAGUAAUUUUAAGGUUUAUAGUUCCCUCAACACAAUUGCUAAUGCAGAAUAGUGUAAAAUGCGCUUCAAGAAUGUUGAUGAUGAUGAUAUAGAAUUGUGGCUUUAGUAGCACAGAGGAUGCCCCAACAAACUCAUGGCGUUGAAACCACACAGUUCUCAUUACUGUUAUUUAUUAGCUGUAGCAUUCUCUGUCUCCUCUCUCUCCUCCUUUGACCUUCUCCUCGACCAGCCAUCAUGACAUUUACCAUGAAUUUACUUCCUCCCAAGAGUUUGGACUGCCCGUCAGAUUGUUGCUGCACAUAGUUGCCUUUGUAUCUCUGUAUGAAAUAAAAGGUCAUUUGUUCA